GCCUCAGUGGUCUACAGCAGUUACACACAGGCAGUGGUAUCUGUGAGCAGCUCUGUGGACUCAAAGGUUUUCUCCCUGAGAGGCAUGACCCAGGCCAGCUGAUUCAUCAGAAUCAGGAUGGACGUGGUAGAGGUCGCGGGCAGUUGGUGGGCACAAGAGCGAGAGGACAUCAUUAUGAAAUACGAAAAGGGACACCGAGCUGGGCUGCCAGAGGACAAGGGGCCUAAGCCUUUUCGAAGCUACAACAACAACGUCGAUCAUUUGGGGAUUGUACAUGAGACGGAGCUGCCUCCUCUGACUGCGCGGGAGGCGAAGCAAAUUCGGCGGGAGAUCAGCCGAAAGAGCAAGUGGGUGGAUAUGCUGGGAGACUGGGAGAAAUACAAAAGCAGCAGAAAGCUCAUAGAUCAAGCGUACAAGGGAAUGCCCAUGAACAUCCGGGGCCCGAUGUGGUCAGUCCUCCUGAACACUGAGGAAAUGAAGUUGAAAAACCCCGGAAGAUACCAGAUCAUGAAGGAGAAGGGCAAGAAGUCAUCUGAGCACAUCCAGCGCAUCGACCGGGACGUAAGCGGGACAUUAAGGAAGCAUAUAUUCUUCAGGGAUCGAUACGGAACCAAGCAGCGGGAACUACUCCACAUCCUCCUGGCAUAUGAGGAGUACAACCCGGAGGUGGGCUACUGCAGGGACCUGAGCCACAUCGCCGCCUUGUUCCUCCUCUAUCUUCCUGAGGAGGAUGCAUUCUGGGCACUGGUGCAGCUGCUGGCCAGUGAGAGGCACUCCCUGCAGGGAUUUCACAGCCCAAAUGGCGGGACCGUCCAGGGGCUCCAAGACCAACAGGAGCAUGUGGUAGCCACGUCACAACCCAAGACCAUGGGGCAUCAGGACAAGAAAGAUCUAUGUGGGCAGUGUUCCCCGUUAGGCUGCCUCAUCCGGAUAUUGAUUGACGGGAUCUCUCUCGGGCUCACCCUGCGCCUGUGGGACGUGUAUCUGGUAGAAGGCGAACAGGCGCUGAUGCCGAUAACAAGAAUCGCCUUUAAGGUUCAGCAGAAGCGCCUCACGAAGACGUCCAGGUGUGGCCCGUGGGCACGUUUUUGCAACCGGUUCGUUGAUACCUGGGCCAGGGAUGAGGACACUGUGCUCAAGCAUCUUAGGGCCUCUAUGAAGAAACUAACAAGAAAGAAGGGGGACCUGCCACCCCCAGCCAAACCCGAGCAAGGGUCGUCGGCAUCCAGGCCUGUGCCGGCUUCACGUGGCGGGAAGACCCUCUGCAAGGGGGACAGGCAGGCCCCUCCAGGCCCACCAGCCCGGUUCCCGCGGCCCAUUUGGUCAGCUUCCCCGCCACGGGCACCUCGUUCUUCCACACCCUGUCCUGGUGGGGCUGUCCGGGAAGACACCUACCCUGUGGGCACUCAGGGUGUGCCCAGCCCGGCCCUGGCUCAGGGAGGACCUCAGGGUUCCUGGAGAUUCCUGCAGUGGAACUCCAUGCCCCGCCUCCCAACGGACCUGGACGUAGAGGGCCCUUGGUUCCGCCAUUAUGAUUUCAGACAGAGCUGCUGGGUCCGUGCCAUAUCCCAGGAGGACCAGCUGGCCCCCUGCUGGCAGGCUGAACACCCUGCGGAGCGGGUGAGAUCGGCUUUCGCUGCACCCAGCACUGAUUCCGACCAGGGCACCCCCUUCAGAGCUAGGGACGAACAGCAGUGUGCUCCCACCUCAGGGCCUUGCCUCUGCGGCCUCCACUUGGAAAGUUCUCAGUUCCCUCCAGGCUUCUAGAAGCAUCUGGGCCAGGGCUCAUGGCUGGAUAAUUUCCCUAGGCUUAACAACCCAAGCAAGCUUCGCAUCCUCGUUUUAUUUUUGGUUAAACUUAUGAAAAUGUAUUAAGAAAGAGUGCAGCUCGAGAGAGAUUCAGAGAUGGAACACACCAGACCCCAGAUCACAAAGCCAACCAUGCCCAGCCCCUCCCAGCACCCCCAGCCCCACGACCAUCGUUCUGAAUUCUGACGACACCGUGAGCCUGCCUUUGUACUUCAAACUCAUGGAAGGAUAACCACCUUCAUGUUUUGAAAUAAAUGUUUCCUGUUGAAAUGA